GUCACUGUACGCUGCCCAGAAACUCUGAGGCGGAUCCCCCAACCCAGUGUCAGACUGAUCGCCUUUGGCCCGAGGGCGAGGAGCCACAGGACAGUAUGGCCAAAGCGGCGGCCUCCUCGUCGCUGGAGGACUUGGACCUGAGCGGAGAGGAGGUCCAGCGGCUCACCUCCGCCUUCCAGGACCCGGAGUUCCGGCGAAUGUUCUCCCAGUACGCCGAGGAGCUCACCGACCCGGAGAACCGGCGGCGCUACGAGGCGGAGAUCACCGCGCUAGAGCGUGAGCGCGGGGUGGAAGUGCGGUUCGUGCACCCGGAGCCCGGCCAUGUGCUGCGCACCAGCCUGGACGGGGCGCGGCGCUGCUUUGUGAAUGUCUGCAGCAACGCGUUGGUGGGCGCGCCCAGCAGCCGGCCCGGCUCCGGUGGCGACCGGGGCGCAGCUCCUGGCAGCCACUGGUCCCUGCCCUACAGCCUGGCGCCCGGCCGCGAGUACGCGGGGCGCAGCAGCAGCCGCUACAUGGUCUACGACGUGGUCUUCCAUCCAGACGCGCUUGCGCUGGCCCGGCGGCACGAGGGCUUCCGCCAGAUGCUGGACGCCACGGCCCUGGAGGCCGUCGAGAAGCAGUUCGGCGUGAAGCUGGACCGCAGGAAUGCCAAGACCCUGAAGGCCAAGUAUAAGGGGACCCCAGAGGCUGCGGUGCUGCGCACGCCCCUGCCCGGGGUCAUCCCCGCAAGGCCUGACGGGGAGCCGAAGGGUCCUCUCCCGGACUUCCCCUACCCUUACCAGUACCCGGCAGCCCCCGGGCCCCGGGCGCCCUCCCCUCCGGAAGCGGCCUUGCAGCCCGCCCCCACCGAGCCUCGCUACAGCGUGGUGCAGCGCCACCACGUGGACCUCCAGGAUUACCGCUGCUCCAGGGACUCAGCCCCGAGCCCCGUGCCCCAUGAGCUGGUGAUCACCAUCGAACUGCCGCUGUUGCGCUCGGCCGAGCAGGCGGCGCUGGAGGUAACGAGAAAGCUGCUGUGCCUCGACUCGAGGAAACCUGACUACCGGCUGCGGCUCUCGCUCCCGUACCCAGUGGACGAUGGCCGCGGCAAGGCACAAUUCAACAAGGCCCGGCGGCAGCUGGUGGUUACGCUGCCAGUGGUGCUGCCGGCCGCGCGCCGGGAGCCCGCUGUCGCCGUCGCCGCCGCCGCGCCGGAAGAGUCCGCGGACCGGUCCGGAACUGACGGCCAGGCCUGCGCUUCCGCUCGCGAGGGGGAGGCGGGACCCGCGAGGAGUCGCGCGGAGGACGGAGGCCACGAUACCUGCGUGGCUGGGGCUGCGGGCUCCGGGGUCACCACCCUGGGCGACCCGGAGGUGGCGCCUCCGCCGGCCGCAGCUGGAGAGGAGCGUGUCCCCAAGCCGGGGGAGCAGGACUUGAGCAGGCACGCGGGGUCACCGCCGGGCAGCGUGGAGGAGCCAUCUCCUGGAGGAGAAAACUCACCUGGUGGCGGAGGCUCCCCUUGUUUGUCCUCCCGGAGCCUGGCGUGGGGUUCUUCUGCGGGAAGAGAGAGUGCGCGCGGAGAUAGCAGUGUGGAAACACGCGAGGAGUCGGAGGGCACGGGCGGCCAGCGCUCAGCCUGCGCCAUGGGUGGUCCCGGGACCAAGAGCGGGGAGCCUUUGUGUCCUCCGUUACUGUGUAAUCAGGACAAAGAAACCUUGACUCUGCUCAUUCAGGUGCCUCGGAUCCAGCCGCAAAGUCUUCAAGGAGAUUUGAAUCCCCUCUGGUACAAAUUACGCUUCUCCGCACAAGACUUAGUUUAUUCCUUCUUUUUGCAAUUUGCUCCAGAGAAUAAAUUGAGUACCACAGAACCUGUGAUUAGCAUUUCUUCAAACAAUGCAGUGAUAGAACUGGCAAAAUCUCCAGAGAGCCAUGGACAUUGGAGAGAGUGGUAUUAUGGUGUAAACAACGAUUCUUUGGAGGAAAGGUUAUUUGUCAAUGAAGAAAAUGUUAAUGAGUUUCUUGAAGAGGUCCUGAGCUCUCCAUUCAAACAGUCUAUGUCCUUGACCCCACCAUUAAUUGAAGUUCUUCAAGUUACUGAUAAUAAGAUUCAAAUUAAUGCAAAGUUGCAAGAAUGUAGUAACUCUGAUCAGCUACAAGGAAAGGAGGAAAGAGUAAAUGAAGAAAGUCAUCUAACUGAAAAGGAAUAUAUAGAACAUUGUAACACCCCUACAACUGAUUCUGAUUCAUCUAUAGCAGUUAAAGCACUACAAAUAGAUAGCUUUGGUUUAGUUACAUGCUUUCAACAAGAGUCUCUUGAUGUUUCUCAAAUGAUACUUGGAAAAUCUCAGCAACCUGAGUCAAAAAUGCAAUCUGAAUUUAUAAAAGAAAAAAGUGCUACUUGUUCAAAUGAGGAAAAAGAUAACUUAAACGAGUCAGUAAUAACUGAAGAGAAAGAAACAGAUGGAGAUCACCUAUCUUCAUUACUGAACAAAACUACGGUUCACAAUAUACCUGGAUUCGACAGCAUAAAAGAAACCAAUAUGCAGGAUGGUAGUGUGCAGGUCAUUAAAGAUCAUGUGACCAAUUGUGCAUUCAGUUUUCAGAAUUCUUUGCUAUAUGAUUUGGAUUAAUUCUAUAUAAUUUUGGACUUUUAAAUAUUAAGGUUAAAAAAUACCUGUAUCUAAAAUUGAUUCUGUUAACUGUUGUCUUAAAACUAAAGGUAUUAAAGUAUAAAAUUAAAAUUUGCAAUUUUUUUUAAAAAAUUGCAAUUUUGAUUCUCAUGGGGGAAAUUGGAGAUAAUUUUUUUUUUUUUGCCUCUGGAGUUUAAAGUUUCCUUAUGGAGAUAAGUUUUGUGAUUCCUGUAAUAGAUGUGUAUGUUUUCUAUUUGAGAGUUAAAACAUUUGAGAGUUAAAACAUUUAGUUUUAAUACAACCUAUGUAUAUAUACUUCUGUGUUAAAUUUUGCUUUGUCAUUAAUAAAAUUUAAAAAUAUUCACUAA